AGUCAGCCGCUCCAGGUGCUUAAGUCUGGACUGCGGAGGCCGGGGCGGUGGCGUGCAGGGUGAGGUCUCCCGGGCUGGCGCGCGUGCAAGCCCCCUGCUGCUACCUCGCGCUAGGCCAGCUCCAGGAGGGCAACAGACGACAGGACAUUGCAAAAGGGCCACUUAAAUUUUCCUUCGAGUAAACAGAACACCUGCCAAGACCCUCGAGCCUGGGCGUGCCCCAAGACAGGUGGUUGGGGUCUAGGAGUCGGCUGCAGCUGGCGAUGCUCUGAGGGGACGUCAGGGCCUCAGGAUCGCCCCUAUGAAGACGAAGUGCAUCUGUGAACUGUGCUCCUGCGGUGCACUGUAACUUGUACCUCUCCUGUACAGUCUUUGAUGCGACGUCUUUCACUCUGGUGAUUACAUGGGACAUGUCUGCACCUUCUCACCCUCCAAACUGGCUGAGCCAUAAGAAGGAAAGCUGACUGAAGGCAGAGGCUGAGGCUGAGUCCUGUAGCUUCUGCAGGAUUAGCGCAGUGCUGGCCACAUAGCAAGCAUGAUCAUGGAUGAGCCCUCAACAGAUGUGAGAGGUUACAAUCUGUAAGAGCAAUGGCUGAAAUGUUGGCCACUUCACUCAUGAUGUUGAAGUUCCUCUUGGACAGGCGGCAUCACUGUCCACAUCUCCCUACCAAGAUUUAUGAUAAAACAGAGAAACCAUGUCUUCUCUCCGAAUAUACCGAGAACUACCCUUUCUAUCACUCCUACCUGCCCAGAGAGUCCUUCAAGCCAAGGCGGGAGUACCAGAAAGGGCCUAUACCAAUGGAAGGCCUGACUACAUCAAGGAGAGAUUUUGGGCCUCACAAAGUGGCACCAGUGAAGGUCCACCAGUAUGACCAGUUCGUCCCGAGUGAAGAGAAUAUGGAUUUGCUCACGACGUAUAAGAAAGAUUACAAUCCCUACCCUGUCUGUCGAGUGGACCCCAUCAAACCUCGGGACAGUAAAUAUCCAUGUAGCGACAAGAUGGAGUGUUUGCCUACUUAUAAAGCUGAUUAUUUGCCUUGGAACCAACCAAGGCGAGAGCCACUUCGUCUGGAACACAAAUACCAGCCGGCAUCAGUCAGGUUUGAUAACAGAACCACACACCAGGACGAUUACCCCAUAAAAGGCCUUGUGAAGACCAUAAGCUGUAAACCUCUGGCCAUGCCAAAGCUCUGUAACAUCCCCUUGGAGGAUGUGACUAACUACAAGAUGAGCUAUGUGGCCCACCCCGUGGAGAAGCGCUUUGUGCAUGAAGCAGAGAAGUUCAGGCCCUGUGAAAUCCCCUUUGAAAGCCUUACCACUCAAAAACAAUCCUACCGGGGCCUGAUGGGGGAGCCUGCCAAGAGCUUGAAACCUCUAGCCAGGCCUCCUGGGCUAGACAUGCCUUUCUGUAACACCACUGAGUUUCGAGAUAAGUACCAAGCUUGGCCAAUGCCCCGGAUGUUCUCCAAAGCUCCCAUCACCUACGUCCCUCCCGAAGACAGGAUGGAUCUUCUGACAACAGUGCAGGCCCAUUACACAUGCCCUAAGGGUGCCCCAGCUCAGUCCUGCCGACCUGCACUUCAGAUUAAGAAGUGCGGUCGCUUUGAAGGCUCUUCCACCACCAAGGAUGACUACAAGCAGUGGUCCAGCAUGCGCACAGAGCCAGUCAAGCCCGUUCCCCAGCUGGACUUGCCCACCGAGCCCCUGGACUGCCUGACCACCACUCGGGCCCACUAUGUGCCCCACCUGCCUAUCAAUACCAAAAGCUGUAAGCCUCAUUGGUCUGGCCCUCGAGGAAAUGUCCCUGUGGAAAGCCAGACCACCUACACCAUCAGCUUUACUCCCAAGGAAAUGGGCAGGUGCCUAGCUUCAUAUCCUGAGCCUCCUGGCUACACCUUUGAGGAAGUGGAUGCUUUGGGUCACAGGAUAUACAAACCAGUUUCCCAGGCAGGCUCUCAGCAGAGCAGCCAUCUUUCUGUAGAUGAUUCAGAAAACCCCAACCAGAGGGAGUUGGAAGUGUUAGCCUGAUUUUGAAAAAUAGUAAUUUAGAAAUUACACAGUACUUUUAAAAGCAGACAACUGAGAAUUAUUUGUUGGACAAAAAAGAAUUCCCUAAAAUGACAAAAAACAAAAAACAAAAAACCUUCACCACUUCCAGAGCACUUGAAUAAAAUGAGAAUCACUUGACUCAGGGAAAAUGACAUUUAAUCACCGGCUAAUUAACUCCCCUUACCUUCUCCUUUACUGCAUCCCCACCCCGUUUCAGGUCCUUUACUUUGUGCUUAUGGAAUCAAAGUUGGUCUGUGAGGGUUUCUCUGAUCCAGAUGUAUUUUAUUAAUUUAAUCAUUGUAUGAACUGACAUAAUGAUUAACCCUUGCCAAGUAUGAAGCGCCAAAGAAUAAAUUUUAUUUUGGGGGGAAUGAAUCUGUA